ACUUGUUGCUAGAGAUACCGCCUGGAGGCCACUGAUCUGUAAAAGGGAUCUCUACAGAAGAUAGGGAUUUUUGAUCGCCAGAGAAGAAGGGAUAUGUGAGAUCCAAACGCCGAAGGAGGAAAGCAGGCUCCGUGGUCUCUUCCAGCCCUGAUGGAAGAAACUACCGAGCCUUAUUAUACUAGGUGCUUUCCACAUGCCUAUUCAUUUAAUCCUCCAGCAACCUUGUAAGAAGGGCCAUCCCAUUUUAUAUUUAAACAAACCUUAACUACUGACGCAAGGAGUCAAGGAUCUAAUCCCAAAGCCUCUGCCUGGUUCGCUGCAGAUGGAUGUCCGCGAGGACGCCAGCCCUCCGCCUCCCGCCGGGUCCCUGAACGCCGGCCCGGCCGGUCCAACCUCAUUCCGCUUCCCGCCAUCGAAACGCGAAGCCCCCGCCUUCCCCCAAACGUCUCAGCGCCGCUGGGGCCUUUCUGGCUGCGCCGCCUCCGACCCCAGGCCCCGGUCCGCGCCCGCCGCUCGCUAGUCCUGGGAGUGAGGAGAACGCGUGCUGAGGACCCGGCCAGAGGGACAGCGGGGACCGCCCUCCCGCUGCGUCUCUGAAAGCGAGGCCGUUCCUCCCGCGUCCGACCCCCGCGGGGCCGUCAGGUUCGGGGCGGCCCAGGCUGCGGGUCCGCAGGGCGCUUCGGGCCGAGCCGGCGCGGCGCGUGAAGGGCAGGGGACGCCCCGAAAGACCGCUGGGGUGGGACCCCAAGCUCCAGGGGUCUUUGGAAAUAAGAAUGCGGCGUGACGUUGGCUGUGCGGGCGCGGGGCUGACGCGGACCCUAUAACCCAUCGCCGAAACCGGGCGGCCGCGCCCCUAUUCCUCGGCAUUUCUCUCUGUCCGCGGCCCUGCUCAGCCAAUCAGCGAGUGGGCUCCUAGGCAGGUCCUGAGUGACAGCGCGGCGGGCUGGAUCAGGAGAUGCGCGUGCGCGGCCCGGCCCGGCUGAUCGCUUCGGGUGCUCGACUCCUGUUGCGCAUGCUCAGCGCGCUGCCCGGCUGGGGACCCGCGCACCUGCAGCGCCCGCUGCUCGGCCCUGCAUCCUGCCUGGGCAUCCUGCGCCCGGCCAUGACGGCGCACUCAUUCGCCCUCCCGGUCAUCAUCUUCACCACGUUCUGGGGCCUCGUCGGCAUCGCCGGGCCCUGGUUCGUGCCGAAGGGACCCAACCGCGGAGUGAUCAUCACCAUGCUGGUCGCCACCGCCGUCUGCUGUUACCUCUUGUUCAGCCCCAACUCGGGGAUCCUGCAGAUCUACCGAACAUCAAAUGAAACCAAAACCAAACCCAGAAGUGCCAUACCAACCCCAUGUGCCUGCCGGAGUGUGGAUGGCUCCCUGGGCCCUUCUUCACCCUGGGAACACAGGCCCUGCCAUCUGCUGGGUUGGCCGCAUCCAAAAUAAUAUGACCGAGGCCUCCCCUGGGUGUGGGAGGACCCUCCUGUGCCAGGCUCACCAUGCUUUGCUGUCCCUGGCAGCUGGCUCAUCGCCAUCCUGGCGCAGCUGAACCCCCUGUUCGGGCCCCAGCUGAAGAAUGAGACCAUCUGGUACGUGCGCUUCCUGUGGGAGUGACCCGCCGCCCCCGACCCAGGUGCCCAGCUCUCGGAAUGACUGUGGCUCCACUGUCCCUGACAACCCCUUCGUCCGGACCCUCCCCCACACAACUAUGUCUGGUCACCAGCUCCCUCCUGCUGGCACCCAGAGACCCGGACCCGCAGGGCCUGCCUGGUUCCUGGAAGUCUUCCCAGUCUUCCCAGCCAGCCCGGGCCCUGGGGAGCCCUGGGCACAGCAGCGGCCGAGGGGAUGUCCUGCUCCAAUACCCGCACUGCUCUGGAGUUUGCCCUCUUUCCCAAGGAGAUGCUGCUGGGGAGCUGGUAUGGGUGGGGUCUUUCCCUUUACAGACGGGGCAGAUGCCAGGACUCAGCCCAUCCUGAGGAGGACACGUGUCCUCAUGGAGAGGGUGCUCCGGCCCAGGCGGGGGAGUCAGUGCCCAGUCAGCAGCUCUGCCACCAUCCUGCUGGGAACUGGGGGGGCCUCUAUUGGGUUAUAGGCAAGGCCUUUUCUCUGGCAUGGAAUUGUUAAUUUUCUGACACGUCUAGAUGUGAAAUUUCUGAAAAUGUUGAAGCAGAGAAACAUUCACACACAAAAAGCAACAUAGUCAUGUGGGUCCAGAUGGCCUCAGUCCUAGAUGUUGGCACCCUUUGCUGUGUCUCCUCAGAGUAUCCUGUUCCGCCUCCUGCCACCUGGACCUCCCUCAGUGGAUGUCUUCCCUCCCCCGACCCCAGCCUGUCAGUCCGAGCACAGUGCAGGUUUGGCUCUGACUUGGGCUUUUGGCUGCAGUGGGGGUGGAUUUCAGAGCCUCUCAUGGCAGCAUCUAAGUGACCAGAGCUGGGAUGAGAGAGGGGAAGGGGCAAUGUGAGUGGCGCUAUGGGACGGGCCAGCCCUGCUCCUGAGCCAGCCCCGCCCUCUGCCCCCUGGCCCUGGGCUCUGUGCUAGGGAUGGUGAAGAAUGGGGGCGUGCCAGCCUGGCAGGAGUGGGAAGCAACACGCAGGGGUCCCGGACCUCUCCAGCCUUGCCCUCACGCUUACCCGAGCUCCCAGUGUGGUUAGCACAGAGCUCACCCACCUUGCCUGGCUCCCAGCUGGGGCCUGUCCUCACUGGUGCUCCAGGGGAAGAAACGACAGCCUCACUUCUGUAUGGACUGCUGAUGUGGCCUGCCAUCCUGUUCAGCGGGCAUUGUCUUUGGAGCAGCAGGAGAAUAGGAUGCCUCUCACUCACAUGCCAGUUCCUGGCUGGCCAGCUGCUCAGGGCUCAGGCUGGGGCCUCCCAUUGACAUCCUCCCCCUACACUCCCUCUCUGAGCCUCCGUCGCCCCUCCUGUUGGGUAAGGGUGUUGAGUGUGACUUGUGCUGAAAACCUGGUUCAUAUAUAAUAAAUAAUGGUGAUGAAAAGA